AGCCCCAGCCCCGGCGAGCACCCAGCUAGCCGCCUCCUGCAGGGGCUCGGGAGAGCAAUUCGGCGGCCCCUGCAGGGCAGCUGAAGCCAUGGAAGCCUCCGCAGGUCGCUGAUCAGGGCCAGGCGGCUGCAGCAGCGACUGCAGAGGCGCUGCGCCAAGCCGGGCCGGAGUGGUGCGAGCCGGCGGGGCUGCGGAGGGCCAGUGGACUCAGGGUUGUUGAGAGGAGUCAAUGGCAUAAUGUACGUAGCGUGGUUGGCACGAGGUCUGGUGUGGCGUGGGGCUCGGUGAAUGCUUCCCUCCAGCAUGGGGAGAGGUCCAGGCAUGACAUCCUCAGCCAAGUCUCCUGUAACCCAGGCUGCUGUCCUCAGUCCCUGCUGUUAAUGUGGAAGGAGGGGACUGAGGUCUCUGGAGCUGGCACAGGACCAGCACAUUGGCUGCAAAGAGCCCAGGUUCCCCACUCUGCCCCAGACUCCGGUAACUUUGGGCUAAUACCCAGUAUAGCCCUCCUCACGACAGCCAAAAUCCAGCCCAGCAUGGGGCCUCUCCCCUCCUUAAAUCCUGGAAAGGCUGCCCUUGGAACCCAAGCCUCUACCCAGGAAAGAAGCCUAAGGACUCGGGGGCAGGAACCAGGGGCUUGAGUCUACCUGCCCACUUAGCAAGAGGCCCAGUGAUGGGUCUCUCUAGGCACGAACGCUUCCUCCUGGGUCCACCCACUGGGACACCCCCAGCGGAGGGCCUCUGCUCCCACCCACCCCAGUGCUCAUCUGCUUUAAGUCUGUGCCCCUACAUUCCUGGUAGAUGCCAAAACCAGCAUGCGCAUUACAUGGGUGGGUGCGGACAUGCCUGUGUGCCGCAUGGGUGCGGGAGGACCUGGCUGCAUGUCCUGCGUCAUGGGCUGGCUGCCUGAGCACGUUCAUGGAGACGCGUGUGGCAUGUCUUGGAAUGGCAGGGACAUGGUACCUUCUCGUGUUGGUGUGUAUCCGUAUGUCUUUCUACACAUGUGCUGGUACGUUGGUCUGUCUUGUCUCCCCUGUAGACGGGAAGCCCCGAACCACGGGCCAACUGGGAAGUUGAUGGUCGGCGAGACCAGCCCAUCCUAAUUUGGGGUUCCUGGUCCUGCUCCAGGAGUCCUACAGCCUGCAGCCCCUACCAGAGAGGGAGGACUGAACAGCAAGGGGCCCCCGGGAUACCGCCCAUCCCACCCCUUACUCGGACCCACAGCCUCAUGGCCAUGUCCCUGCCAGGAAGUAGACGGACCUCUGCUGGAUCACGCAGGCGCACCUCUCCACCUGUGAGCGUGCGGGAUGCCUACGGCACCUCUUCGCUCAGCAGCAGCAGCAAUUCUGGCUCCUACAAGGGCAGUGACAGCAGUCCCACGCCAAGGCGCUCCAUGAAAUACACGCUGUGCAGUGACAACCAUGGCAUCAAGCCCCCGACCCCGGAGCAGUACCUGACCCCCCUGCAGCAGAAGGAGGUGUGCAUCCGGCACCUGAAAGCCCGGCUGAAGGACACACAGGACCGGCUCCAGGACCGGGACACAGAGAUUGAUGACCUGAAGACGCAGCUGUCACGCAUGCAGGAGGACUGGAUUGAGGAGGAGUGCCACCGCGUGGAGGCCCAGCUGGCCCUGAAGGAGGCCCGAAAGGAGAUCAAGCAGCUCAAGCAGGUCAUCGACACUGUCAAGAACAACCUGAUUGACAAGGACAAGGGGCUGCAGAAGUACUUCGUGGACAUCAACAUCCAGAACAAGAAGCUGGAGACGCUGCUGCACAGCAUGGAGGUGGCCCAGAAUGGCAUGGCCAAGGAGGAUGGCACUGGGGAGUCAGCCGGUGGGUCCCCUGCCCGCUCCCUCACCCGCAGCUCCACCUACACCAAGCUGAGUGACCCGGCUGUCUGUGGUGACCGCCAGCCGGGUGAUCCCUCCAGCGGCUCUGCUGAGGAUGGGGCAGACAGUGGCUUUGCAGCAGCCGAUGACACACUGAGCCGGACGGACGCGCUGGAAGCCAGCAGCCUGCUGUCGUCGGGGGUGGACUGUGGCACCGAGGAGACCUCGCUGCACAGCUCCUUCGGCCUGGGCCCCCGCUUCCCUGCCAGCAACACCUAUGAGAAGCUGCUGUGUGGCAUGGAGGCUGGUGUGCAGGCCAGCUGCAUGCAGGAGCGUGCCAUCCAGACAGACUUCGUGCAGUACCAGCCUGACCUUGACACCAUCCUGGAGAAAGUGACCCAGGCCCAGGUCUGUGGGACAGACCCUGAGUCAGGGGACAGGUGCCCAGAGCUGGAUGCCCACCCUUCAGGGCCCAGAGACCCCAACUCAGCAGUGGUGGUGACAGUGGGUGAUGAGCUAGAGGCCCCAGAGCCCAUCACCCGUGGACCCACCCCACAGCGGCCUGGUGCCAACCCCAACCCUGGCCAGUCGGUGAGCGUGGUGUGCCCCAUGGAAGAGGAGGAGGAGGCUGCCGUGGCUGAGAAGGAGCCCAAGAGCUACUGGAGCCGCCACUACAUCGUGGAUCUGCUGGCUGUGGUGGUGCCGGCCGUGCCCACGGUGGCCUGGCUUUGCCGCUCCCAGCGGCGCCAGGGCCAGCCCAUCUACAACAUCAGCUCCCUGCUGCGGGGCUGCUGCACUGUGGCCUUGCACUCCAUCCGCAGGAUCAGCUGCCGCUCGCUGAGCCAGCCGAGUCCCAGCCCAGCGGGCGGCGGCUCCCAGCUCUGAGGGGGCCCAUUCUGGCAGCGGCGCCUGCGGCCUGACCACUGAUUGUAGGGAUGCCGUUCCCCCCUCCCUUCUCCCAUGGGCAUCAUCUUAUUUAUUUAGUUUUGGGUGUGGAACUGUUUCUUUUUUUCAAGAUGUUAAAACAGUCCCGUGGAAGGAGCAGGGGUUGGAGAAAGGCAUCCCAAAGCUUCGAUGGAGAGCAGGGAAGGGGGACCCAAGGCAGGAGGUACACCAGCUGGACAAAUUGCAGGGAGGGGAGGGAGCGAGGGCCAACCCGGCCCCUCUGUCCCCUUGGCUCUUCAGACAGGGCCAGCCCUGCUCAGGAAGUCUCUGGCUGUCUUCAUGUGGGGAAGCCGGGCUUGAGUUGCCCAUAGGCCCCUGCCCUGCACCAUCCUGUCCAGUGCCCUGCGCACUCCAUGCCGUCUCUUCCAAGCCACCUUGCCCGCAGCCCAGGCUCCUGGGCCAGUGCUCUCUCCUCAAAUGGAGGCAGCCAUGGCCUGAAGUGCAGAUCACUGACCCAGGGCUCAGAGCAGAGGCCAGAACCACUGGGCCGGCCGGCAUUCCAGCCUCCCCAGACUGCUGCCCACCUUGGGACUCAGGAGCUCAGUCAAGGCCACAGGCUGGAGGAGAGACGGGGCUGGGCGCAAGGUGGCGGAGGGCAGUGUGGGUUCUGUGUCUGUCUGUUCAUCCCAGGCUUUCCCGUCAUCCCUUUCCUCUUGGCACUUCUGGGUGUGUCAGUCAUUAUUCCUGUGAGGUAGCUAAGCCCGGCAAGCUCAGUGCUGGGGUAGGAGGGCCUGCCUGAGUCCCAGCUCCCAGCUGGAGAAUCCACCAGCACAAGAAGAGGAGGCAGGGGCAGAAACCCAAGGGGGCUCCCCCAGCCUUCCAAGGUGAGGCCAUCUCAUCUGCAGGCUGGGAGGCAGGGCUGGACUCAGGAACCCACAGCUUACUGAAAAAGCCAGAGGCCAUGACUGCCCCCAGAAACUUGCCCCGAGUUUCUCUGGGGCCCUCGGGCCCAACUUCUGCUUUGCACUAUGUUCACUUUGGGGUUGGUUCUCAGCCAUCCAAGGGUCUCCAGUGAGGUGGCUGCUUGCUGUCUGAGAUGAGGGUUCCUAAACCUUAAACCUCUCUGCCUCUGGAGGAGGGUGGGGUAUUCUGGCAGGAUGAAUCGCAGGAUGGCGCGUACUGAAGCCACGAUGUUCAUCCAGGCCAAAGCAGGGUGUCCUGGGAUAGGUUUCCUAGGCAGGGGCGUGGCAGAGCAGGUAGGCGCCCUGCAGCCUCCCUGCUCCCAGCCCAAGGCCAGUCGGCCUGGGAAGUUCACUGCCCCAACUCUUUUCCCGGGACCAUACUGAGUCCCCCAGCCACGCUGCUGACAUUACCAUUAUUAUUUUACCAAGUAAACUCACUCCUUUUCCCCCACAGGGGUUACACCCAUCUGGUUGUCCCACCCACUCUUCAGAGGCUAGGCCCCACCUCUGGGGGUUGGAGGGACCCUGUGUCUUACUCGCCCCUCUGGCCUAAGGGCCACUCUGGUUAUCUGCCAAGGUUGCUUGCCCUCACCCCAAUGCUCCAACAGCCAUUGCCUAACUCAUGGGCUCUGCCCUUCUGCUCGGUGCCCUCCACGUGAGGCGGGGCACCUGCAUGCACUGGGAGGGGGCGGCUGGCCCAGCCCUCGGGGCAGGAGCCCCCUCUGCCACACGCUUUGUGCCUCCAAAGCUCCCCCCGCCUUGGUCAGGGCCUCAGACCAGCCAACCUUUGUGGAAUAAGCCCCAGCCCAGCCAAACCAAACCCAGAUGCCUGAGGCCUGGCUGGGGCUGCCCCCGCAGGACACUGUGGCCAUGCCACGGAGGGGGCAGUGGACAAAACCAAUCCAAAGCCAAGCCGGGACUGGCUGCGGACCCAGCCUCCUGUGCCGCGCACUCACGGAGCUGCGUAGUCUCCUCAGACAUAGUCAAAGCUUUGCCGAGAAAAGAAAUGUAUGAACUAUAUUUGACAACAUAAAAUCUCUCUAUUUUUCACCACUGGAAUUUAGUCAAGCUUCAGGCCCCUCUGCUCCUGUCUGUGUCUUGCGUCUGUGGCCUUCCUAUUGUGUCUUGUGUUUUGGUGGAUGUGACAGGGCUGGGGCCACAGUCUACUCUGUCUCUGCUGCUAGAGAAGCCACCUGUGGAGGACUGGGCUGUGGUUGGGCCUGAGGCCUGUGGAGGAGGUGAGUGUAGCCAGCAGCGGCCGUCUACUCCUGUUCUGGCCUGAGACCACCGGUGUGGGUCACGAGGGCCCUGGCCCACAGUGUUGAGGGUCCUCUCUUUCGGGGGCUCUCCUGGGGCCUUCGAUGGGCUUUUCUUCUUGUCAGUGGAGGGAGCAGCUCCCCACUCAGCCCUGGGACAGGCCCUGGGACUGUGGUGGCCGGUGGCCCUGGCCCAGCUCUGGAGUGCAUGUGUGUGUGCUCAGAUCCCGCAUCUAUGCAAAGGUGCAGGCUGCCUGUGAGGCUCCAGGCGGUGGAGGUGCGGCAGCUGCUGCUCAGGUGCCAUGCCCUGAAGAGGCAGGGUACACAUGGGGCUGGGAGGGCAAAGAUGGGGCGGGGCCUCCCCCUGAGAGAGCUCACCCUCCACAGUGACCCUUUUCCUUCCUGCCUAAUACCUCCUCCCGUUGGGCUGUGACUUUUCCUCCUGCCCUCAGCCUCUGAAACAGAAAUCUUUGGGGCCUCCCCUUUCCCCAGCGUCUGGCAAGAGCUGAUGAGGUCCUGAGGAACAGUGUCCCCAGGAACCACCUUCUGGAGCCUAGCGGCCAGACGUGGCUUCUCCUGAGUUCUAGGGCUCGGGCCAGAGUGGCACUACUGCCCGGCCAGUCCAGGCUCAGGCAGGAAUCGGACGCUGGGGCCCGGGCUCUGCACAGAGAGCUGGGCUUGAGUGGAGUUUAUUGUAGAUUUCUCCCAAGGGGAUCACUUAGCUUCUCACUGACACACCCUUCCCAAUUGCCACAAGCGCAGGGGUAUCUUACAGCACUUUGGGGAGGGGUGGGACAAACUGCAAGGUUCUGGGGCCAAGGCCUACCCAGGGGCCUCUGCCCAGAGAACUCACAACCCCCUCUCUGACCUGGGGGACAAUGCAAACAGGUCACAGUGCAUUCCCAUAUUAGGCCAUCCCCUUCACGAAGAAUUCAGGGGAUGUGGGAAGUGGGGAGGCGGGGAGGGAUCUUGACUCUUGUCUCCUUUGUCCUUUUGUUCAGACAGAGUUGUACCUGCAGCAGACAACUCUGAAUUAAAGCAUGAAAACACAGCAA